AGUUGACGCUCUGGGCCGCCACCUCCGCGGACCCUGAGCGCAAGAGCCAAGCCGCCAGCGCUGCGAUGUGGGCCACGCUGCCGCUGCUCUGCGCCGGGGCCUGGCUCCUGGGAGUCCCCGUCUGCGGUGCCGCCGAACUGUGCGUGAACUCCUUAGAGAAGUUUCACUUCAAGUCAUGGAUGUCUAAGAAAACCAAAGCACACUGUGUACUGGUUGCAGAAUCAGUUGGGGAACACCAGUGCAUGUGCUUUUGAAAAAUGGUGAUCUUUGCUGUAAACUUGACCCAGCACCAGCAGUGGCGUCCAGGAGUGCCCCACAUGUGGCAGCACCGUAAGACCUACAGUACGGAGGAGUACCACCACAGGCUGCAGACGUUUGCCAGCAACUGGAGGAAGAUAAACGCCCACAACAAUGGGAACCACACAUUUAAAAUGGCACUGAACCAAUUUUCAGACAUGAGCUUUGCUGAAAUAAAACACAAGUAUCUCUGGUCAGAGCCUCAGAAUUGCUCAGCCACCAAAAGUAACUACCUUCGAGGUACUGGUCCCUACCCACCUUCCGUGGACUGGCGGAAAAAAGGAAAUUUUGUCUCACCUGUGAAAAAUCAGGGUGCCUGCGGCAGUUGCUGGACUUUCUCCACCACUGGGGCCCUGGAGUCUGCGAUCGCCAUCGCAACCGGAAAGAUGCUGUCCUUGCAGCCUCAGUUGUCUUCAUGAGGGAAGAGCCGGGACCUAUGCAUCCAUCCCCUCGCCCACAAGAGACGGAUGAUGCCCCUGAAGGAACUAUCCUAGCCCCUGCCUCUGUGGAGAAAGGAGGGACAGUGCACAGCCGGCCUGGUGAUGCCAUGAGGACCCUGGGUUGUGGACAGGUGGGGGUAGGGUCUCUGGCUGGGCCUGUUUCCCCCAUCCUAUACACCGCUGUGGGACCCCACACUCUGCAUCGUAUGGGCACACCUACGGGGCAGGGGUUUGGACCCAACAGCCCUUGCCCCCUCUCACCUUCCCUGGCUGCCCCUGCUUACUGAGCCCCUCCCGACAUGUGCCAGCUGCUGGGCUGGCACUGCAGGACAUACAGCAACUGUCCCUGCCCUUGGGGAGUUUAUAAUUUGGUCACCUUGACACAGCACUGACGGGGCCUCAGAUGUGGCUCAGCCAGGGAGGCUUAGCGCCUCACGCCAAAGCCUUGACGGCUUCUCAGCUGGCAGGUCACUGGGUUGUGUCCUUCUUCCAGGCGGAACAGCAGCUGGUGGACUGCGCCCAGGACUUCAAUAAUCACGGCUGCCAAGGGGGUCUCCCCAGCCAGGCUUUCGAGUAUAUCCUGUACAACAAGGGGAUCAUGGGUGAAGACACCUACCCCUACCAGGGCAAGGAUGGUUAUUGCAAGUUCCAACCUGGAAAGGCCAUCGGCUUUGUCAAGGAUGUAGCCAACAUCACAAUCUAUGACGAGGAAGCGAUGGUGGAGGCUGUGGCCCUCUACAACCCUGUGAGCUUUGCCUUUGAGGUGACUCAGGACUUCAUGAUGUAUAGAACCGGCAUCUACUCCAGUACUUCCUGCCAUAAAACUCCAGAUAAAGUAAACCAUGCAGUACUGGCUGUUGGGUAUGGAGAAAAAAAUGGGAUCCCUUACUGGAUCGUGAAAAACUCUUGGGGUCCCCAGUGGGGAAUGAACGGGUACUUCCUCAUCGAGCGCGGAAAGAACAUGUGUGGCCUGGCUGCCUGCGCCUCCUACCCCAUCCCUCUGGUGUGAGCCGUGGCAGCCGCAGCGCAGACUGGCGGAGAAGGAGAGGAACGGGCAGCCUGGGCCUGGGUGGAAAUCCUGCCCUGGAGGAAGUUGUGGGGAGAUCCACUGGGACCCCCAACAUUCUGCCCUCACCUCUGUGCCCAGCCUGGAAACCUACAGACAAGGAGGAGUUCCACCAUGAGCUCACCCGUGUCUAUGACGCAAAGAUCACCAGCCAUGUGCCUUAGUGUCCUUCUUAACAGACUCAAACCACAUGGACCACGAAUAUUCUUUCUGUCCAGAAGGGCUACUUUCCACAUAUAGAGCUCCAGGGACUGUCUUUUCUGUAUUCGCUGUUCAAUAAACAUUGAGUGAGCACCUCCCCAGAUGGAGCAUGCUGGUCCUGGGCCAUGACUCAAACCAGGUCUGUCCUCGCCACUCAGUCUCCCAGGAGGGAGGCAUCAGGGGGUGUCCAGGCUCUGGCUGGGAGGAUGGUGGGGGUGCUGGCGGUAUUAUCCACCAGAUGGGGUAUCCAGGAUGAAGAGCAGGCUUAAUUUGAGAUCUUGACUAUUUGUCCCAAACCUGAGUGGAGAGGUGGGGAGGAAGGAGAAAAACGGGCCAAGCUGCGGCAGAGGCAGGAUUCAAACCCACAAUGUCAGCCCAGAAGCCUGUACUUCUCUGUGUGGCCUCCCCAGUCUCAGCUGCCUACUCCUACUCAGACUCUGCCCCCCACCUCCACAUGAGACUGCCCACCCCUUCCUCACCAACCCCUUAUUUAUUUCAAACGUGCCCAGAUGCUCCUGUCGUUUCCACACCAUCCCUUCCCUUAUCUUGCCUUUUGAGAAAUCUUGAUCUCUGUUUAGAGGGCGGCCAUGAAGUUGCUGCUGCUUCCUGAAGCCUCCGGGCUCUGGGAUGUCUGUAGAACAAGCUGGAGUCCACCAGCUCUUUGUCCUAUGGCUCACAGACUUUCUUAAUGAUAAAAGCUGUCAUCUUAUUUGGGCUUCCUGAAAAGCUAAAGGCUUGAGAAUAUUUGAAAAAUAUAUAUGUUCAUGAUAAGGCUUAUUUAGAUAAUGCAAAUAUAGUUUAAUUUAUUAGAAAA